AAUGUAUGUUAAAAUAUUCAAAGAAUAAAGAGGUUUUUUAAAGAAUAGUAGGUUCUAGCACGGCUCAGUUAAAAUAUGGUAUCACUUAGUAAGAAACACUUUCUAAAAAACAAUUUAUAUUAGCCAUAAUUAAGAAAAAAAGGGAUAUUGAAUAAGUCAAAGAGUGGUUUCCAGGGAAGUCUUUCUUUGUCUGGAAAGAUACCAUAGGAUUUUCUGCAGACAGCUUACUCAUUUUUUUCUUGAUUGAAAUCUGGAAAGGAAAACUUGCAAGAAAACAUUCCAUUCUGGACUCGGCAGCAGGUCAAGCCAAAGUGGCAACAUUUGCAGCCUGGAGAUCACACAGUCUGGGAGCUCAAACAUUUAGGCAAUAAAAGCUGAUGGAAGCCAAAAAGCCACGCCACUGGCAUCUGGUGUCAGGGUAGCUGCUGGGGGAGAUCUGGCCAUGGUGGUGGGGCCCAGCCAUAUAAACAAGUUCAGAGGUAGAACUGGAGCUGUGUACUGGGUUGAAGCAUGUCUCUCCUAAAUUCAUGUUUUCUCUAGAACCUUAGACUAUGACCUUAUUUGGAAAUAGGGUCUUUGCGAUGUCAUGCAUUGCUUAACAUUGUGGUUACAUUCUGAGUAAUGUGUUGUUAGGUGAUUUCAUCAUUGUCCAAACAUCAUAGAGUGUACUCACACAAACCUAGACGGUACAGUCUCCUACACACCUAGACCAUAUACUAUAUCCUAUUGUUCCUAGGCUGCAAACCUCUACAGCCUGUUACUGUACUGACUACUGUAGGCAAUUGGGGUACAAUAAUCUAAUGAGACUAUAAUCAUAUAUUUAGUGUGCCAUUGACCGAAAUGUCAUUAUGAUGCAUGACUGUAGUUAAGAUGAGGUCAUACUGGAUUAGGUAGGUUCUAAAUCCAAUGUGACUAGUGUCCUCAUAAGAGGAGAGAAACAGACACAAACACAGGGAAACACCGGGACGAUGGCCAUCUGAAGACAGAGGCAAACAUUGGAGUGAUGCAAUGACAAGCCAAGGAAUGCCAAGGACUGCAAACCAUUGCCAGAAGCUAGGAACACUCAAGACAUUUGUGUACUCACUGCUCAAUCGAGGGAGGCCUUAUCCAGCUAUACUCAUUCUCAGAGGCACUGCCUUCUGCACUGGAAAUGGAGUCCUUCAAGGCUACUAUCUGAUUUACUGUGCUGAAUACCCUGAUGGGUGGUACACAGACAUACGGUUUAGCUUGGGUGUCUUCUUAUUUAUUUUGGGAAUGGGAAUAAACAUUCAUAGUGACUAUAUAUUGCGCCAGCUCAGGAAGCCUGGAGAAAUCAGCUACAGGAUUCCACAAGGUGGCUUGUUUACGUAUGUUUCUGGAGCCAAUUUCCUCGGUGAGAUCAUUGAAUGGAUCGGCUAUGCCCUGGCCACUUGGUCCCUCCCAGCACUUGCAUUUGCAUUUUUCUCACUUUGUUUCCUUGGGCUGCGAGCUUUUCACCACCAUAGGUUCUACCUCAAGAUGUUUGAGGACUACCCCAAAUCUCGGAAAGCCCUUAUUCCAUUCAUCUUUUAAAGGAACCAAAUUAAAAAGGAGCAGAGCUCCCACAAUGCUGAUGAAAACUGUCAAGCUGCUGAAACUGUAAUUUUCAUGAUAUAAUAGUCCCGUAUAUAUGUAAUAGUAGGUCUCCUGGCGUUCUGCCAGCUGGCCUGGGGAUUCUGAGUGGUGUCUGCUUAGAGUUUACUCCUACCCUUCCAGGGACCCCUAUCCUGAUCCCCAACUGAAGCUUCAAAAAGCCACUUUUCCAAAUGGCGACAGUUGCUUCUUAGCUAUUGCUCUGAGAAAGUACAAACUUCUCCUAUGUCUUUCACCGGGCAAUCCAAGUACAUGUGGCUUCAUACCCACUCCCUGUCAAUGCAGGACAACUCUGUAAUCAAGAAUUUUUUGACUUGAAGGCAGUACUUAUAGACCUUAUUAAAGGUAUGCAUUUUAUACAUGUAACAGAGUAGCAGAAAUUUAAACUCUGAAGCCACAAAGACCCAGAGCAAACCCACUCCCAAAUGAAAACCCCAGUCAUGGCUUCCUUUUUCUUGGUUAAUUAGGAAAGAUGAGAAAUUAUUAGGUAGACCUUGAAUACAGGAGCCCUCUCCUCAUAGUGCUGAAAAGAUACUGAUGCAUUGACCUCAUUUCAAAUUUGUGCAGUGUCUUAGUUGAUGAGUGCCUCUGUUUUCCAGAAGAUUUCACAAUCCCCGGAAAACUGGUAUGGCUAUUCUUGAAGGCCAGGUUUUAAUAACCACAAACAAAAAGGCAUGAACCUGGGUGGCUUAUGAGAGAGUAGAGAACAACAUGACCCUGGAUGGCUACUAAGAGGAUAGAGAACAGUUUUACAAUAGACAUUGCAAACUCUCAUGUUUUUGGAAACUAGUGGCAAUAUCCAAAUAAUGAGUAGUGUAAAACAAAGAGAAUUAAUGAUGAGGUUACAUGCUGCUUGCCUCCACCAGAUGUCCACAACAAUAUGAAGUACAGCAGAAGCCCCAAGCAACUUUCCUUUCCUGGAGCUUCUUCCUUGUAGUUCUCAGGACCUGUUCAAGAAGGUGUCUCCUAGGGGCAGCCUGAAUGCCUCCCUCAAAGGACCUGCAGGCAGAGACUGAAAAUUGCAGACAGAGGGGCACGUCUGGGCAGAAAACCUGUUUUGUUUGGCUCAGACAUAUAGUUUUUUUUUUUUUUACAAAGUUUCAAAAACUUAAAAAUCAGGAGAUUCCUUCAUAAAACUCUAGCAUUCUAGUUUCAUUUAAAAAGUUGGAGGAUCUGAACAUACAGAGCCCACAUUUCCACACCAGAACUGGAACUACGUAGCUAGUAAGCAUUUGAGUUUGCAAACUCUUGUGAAGGGGUCACCCCAGCAUGAGUGCUGAGAUAUGGACUCUCUAAGGAAGGGGCCGAACGCUUGUAAUUGGAAUACAUGGAAAUAUUUGUCUUCUCAGGCCUAUGUUUGCGGAAUGCAUUGUCAAUAUUUAGCAAACUGUUUUGACAAAUGAGCACCAGUGGUACUAAGCACAGAAACUCACUAUAUAAGUCACAUAGGAAACUUGAAAGGUCUGAGGAUGAUGUAGAUUACUGAAAAAUGCAAAUUGCAAUCAUAUAAAUAAGUGUUUUUGUUGUUCAUUAAAUACCUUUAAAUCAUGGAUGUUAAGCAGUUUUGUUUGAAUUAAAAUAUCCUGGGACUUCUGGAGAUUUUCACAAGGUAUUGGGGUGUGCUUCCCUGUCCCGCCUGUCCCUCAUUCCCAUUCACCCUGUCUGUAGUGUCGUUUCCUUUCUUCUCUUCUCUCUUCAUGAAAUUAGGGGCUGUGUGCUGGAAAUAAAGAAGUAUGACUUAUACAGCCUCUCAGCCACAAUUCAGAACUACAAGGAAGUACAAUAAAGGUGCAGGAAAACGUCAUGAGGUUAGAUGCCACUCCUGGUGCUGAGGAAUACACAGGGGGAAUGAACACACUUGGUGAAGUAAAUCUUCAGGUGUAGCUUGAGCUCUGUGACAUAAAAGACUUCCAGUUCUCUCCAUGACAUUGAAAACUACCUUGCUUAAGUCCUUUAUUUUACUACCAUGUAAAACAUCCAGGCCGGUCCUUGAGAUGAAAUAAAUAUACAAUAAAUGGCAGUACUCAGUCUCAGGACAAAACCGCCAUUUGGCAAUUUCACUUUUUGCCACAAGAGGGCGCUUUCUAAAAUAGUAUUUAGUCCAACCUUGACUUAAUUAGGUCCAACCCCAGUCCUGUUGCCUGAUCGUGGACCUUUCAAGUUAGCAUGAUCGUGGAACUUCUUAAUCUGAAUAUAGGGUAGAGUAGCGUGAACUCUAUGAAAGCUGAAACCUUCCCUUGAUAAUUCAGGUAUUCUCAGUGUUCUAGGGCUGUUGUGUUCAAUGACAGUUUGUCAUUGUUUAGGGCUAGGAUAUGUAUGUGGAUUAAAUACAGUAAAGGUCUGAACAUGUGCUCAUCUCUAAACAUAUUUCUUCCCACUUUUAAAAAUAGGGUGCAACAAAAUUAUAGUUAAUUGAGGUUUCCAUGGACUGUUUUUUGGCUAAAAUAAUCUAACAGUGUCCUAGCUCACAAGAUACUCUAUCUUGGUCUUGCUGAAGCUUUCACGGAAGAGGCGUUUUCCUGCCAACCUUGAAGAAAAUGUUGAGUUUUGUUUGUUUUUCAGAAUUUAGACUUAAAGAGCUGAAGCAGACCUCAGACAUCAGCUAUUCCUACCACUUCACAUUAUAGGUAGUGACACUGAGACCCACAGAGUUAAAAGGCCUCCUCACAGCUGGUACAGAGCUGGUCAGAGCAGCCAUCUCAUUUUGUCCCUUUGAGGGUCAGAUGUAUGCUUCUUCUGCUUAAGGCACAGCCUUUAGGGCUGCCAUCUGGAUUUCUACAGAGCUCAUGCAGGAGAAAAAUAGCCAGAGCUUAAGUGCUGUUGCAUAGUUCAGUUUAUACACCUAUUGUCCCAUGCCUGUUUGUGUGUGAGGCUUCCCUCGCUCCGUGGGAGCACCAGGCUCAUGCCCUUUCAUAAACCUAUUUGACAGAAUAGAGAGUUUUCCCUCAUUGGUGUAGUCAAGACAACAUGUGUGUUCAGCAUGGAAAAAAGGUUUCAGGUCAUAAACCCCCUUAUCCCUAAUGCUUACUUUCAUAAAGAACAACAGUGGCUCCACUGUAUUCUAAAAGGAAAAAGGAGCUCUAAUGAGAAAUACGCAAUUAAACAGCUAUUUAGGCGGCUUAGACCCUUUCAGGAACAAAUAAAUAAAUCCGUGGUUUUACAACCCUGAAGUUUGAUAAUAGCUCUCUUGGAUUUUUGUGGUUACCUCAUGGCAAUCUCACUAAGAAGCAGGGGAGCAAGCUCUUGGCACAUGAAGGAAUAGGCUCAUGAAGAUUCAUUUCUUUUCCCGCUUGGCCUUUUGGUUCUCUAAUAAGCUGUGAGCUGAGGUCCAUGCAGGGAAAACAAGGAGGGUAACGGCAAAUGUAAAGUGAAUUUUUCUGGAGAAGGAUGCUGAUUAUUUUAUAGCAUCUACACUAUCCUAUGAUGAAAGAGGCAUAGAGCCGGGUGGCAAUGUGAGUUCUUGGGUGAUUUAAUAAGCCAUCGAGUGGAUUUAAUUUCUAAGUAAGACAUUUGUUUAUUCUUUGUACAAGUCCAUGGAGUUGUGAUCUUAAAGAGUUCUGUGUUAUUUGCAUUGUGCCUCAUUUCUCCCCAUCAACCUUAGCUUGAGAUUUGGAUGAAUAAAAUAAAUAACUGGAGAAGGUUAAAGUAUGCACCAA